AUACAGCCCAAGAGCAUUCUUUGGGCUCUCUGAACCUCUGCUUCCAGGAAGGCGGUCAUACAAAAAUGAAGGCUGUGAGCUAAUGGCUGUAAACAAAUACACUUGCAGCAGGUUAUGAGGCCACCUUUCAACCUUCAGCACAUCCACUGGAGGUAGGUAUUUUUGAGACUACUCUCAAAAAAUUUUUUCUUAAGGCCUACGUGAUAAACCUUGUUCCCUAAUGGGGAUGAGAAUUGGAUUAGGCUGUAAGAUUAGCCUAGGGGAACAGCAGGCUGGGUGGGGGGUUGGGGACAUCCUGCUUAGGGGUAGCCAGCCAAAGUCCCCCAUACAAGCCCAACCAAGGAUCAUGCCACAUUGAAGGUCUGCACAGUAGUGAGGCAGUGCUGUGGAAUGACAUCUGCCUUCCAACUUCUUACGUGAGUAAGGAGGCUCUCCCUGAAUAUUCAGAUGGAUGUUCAGCCACAUUCUUUGCUAUAUUUAUAGGGUGGGGAGGGAAGACAAGGGGGAGCCAGGGAGUCCGAGCUGUUUAGAGAGGAGAGAAGGAAGUUUCAACAAUGGGUAGGUUCAGGCUGUGGUUCCUCCUCACUGCCCCUUCCUCUUUGAGUUUGUCAGGGGACCUUCCUAUGGCCUGAGAUCAUUUUCUUUUUCAAAGUGGCCAAAGCCACUGUAGGCACAUUUAAAUCAGGGUGCUUUAGCAGAAAUACCAAUGCUGGCAUCUAAAACCCAUGUGUAGUGAGACUUGAUUGACAUUUGGGACCUUUUUAAAACUGUAAUUUUAUUGUAUUUUUGCAUUUCCUGGUUUGUUAAUCAAGGAAGAACAUUGGCAUGUCAUCUUCCAGUCUCCAAAUGUAAGUUAAAUUGUCAAUUUGUGUUUUUCCAGAAAAUUUCUUUUUCCAGAAGUGCUUUGAAUCAUGAUCAUCUAUCUGUAGGCAUGGAUCCUCCAAUUUAGAAGUUGCUCCUAGUGUUACCUAGUUACCCUUCCUGUUCCAUUCUGUGAAACUGGGAGAUUUACUGUAGAUUAUUCAGUCUGGUCAGACAGAAAACUGCAGCUCCCUCCCCAGUCAACCAAAGCCUCCUCUAUGGAGGGGAGGUAUGGUAAUGACAUUAUCUUUCCUUAGGCAGCCGCGUGUUCUCUGAGAACAGGAUGUGGGGAGGGCUGGGCCCCAGUCACAGGGUAUGGGGGUGGGCACCGGAAAAUGGGCUGGUGGUAAGGCCAUGAGGAUUAGUGCUUGCCUUCUUGGCUUUGAGAGGCAUGAAGAGCUCCUGUAUUCUUGAUUGUUCACUCAUGUGUACACCCCACCCUCGCACAUGGCAUGUCUGUGUUCUUACCCUAAGAAAGACUGUACCUGAGAAACACCUUGUGUAAGAGCCCCAGCUGUUUGGCUUGCAGAAACUCAGUGAGGUGGAGUGAGUGGGCCCAGGCUGCUCACUGUACCAACCCAUGCCUUGUGAUUCUUUAUGACAGCCUGUGGCUUCAGGCCACUUUUGCUAAGCUUUAUUGGGGAGCUGGGCCCCAGUAGAUAAUGGGCAGCUUUGCUGCUCUUUCUCAGGGCCCCAGUUGUUUCCCUCCCCACAAAUGGCUCCUUAGCUGAGGUGAUUUGCAUGUUCAACUUCCUUUCAGGCCCCAUCCUUCUCUUCUCCCUGCCCCCCACUGCUUCUGCUGGGGACCUGUGGUGAUGUUCUGCCUGGGGUGGGGAAAAGAGGAUGUAGCUAGCUUCCUGUGCAAAAGAGGGUGGGGCGCCGGCCUUCCUGCCUGUCUGCCCACCCACCCAGUGCUUGAGGAAUUGCCUGAAGAGUUCAGUUCAGAGUCACCAGAGCCUGAAGGGCUUUCUUCAGAGUAGAGAUUGACCUUUGCUCAUGCUGGUCUCUCUCCACAGUUUUCUACUGUGGGAAUAGCUGGACACUUUUUUCCUGAAAUCGCAAUGCUGAAAGGACCUUUAGAGGCCAACUAGACCAACCACUUCACAUUACAGAUGGGGAAACUGAAGCCCAGAAAGUCAUAUAAGUCCUAUAAGGAAUCAGUGGCAAAGCUAGGAUGAGUAGAAUUCUAGAAGGUCAGACCUAGGGCUCUCUCCCUCCCGUCAAGCUGCUAAUCCAGUGGGUUACAAACUGUUUGGCUGGGCUACCUGGUGAGCUACAGCCUCCCUUCAACCAGAACAGCUCUACUUUUACGUACUUCAUAUUUUGAAGUUUUGUGUGAUUUUCUGUUUGGGAGAUUGAGGAGGCAGGAAGCUGUUAGAAAUGUAAUAAAGUCAAAACCACUGAGCAAAACCCAGCCAUUACAGUUGGGAACACUCAGACCUACAGGGGGAAGUAAAUAUCCGAAGUUUACUGGGAUUGGACUCAGAGACCCAAUCUCUGAACCACCAUUCAUGGCUGGUUGCUCCGAGCUAAAGAUGUGGCUCCUUCUACCACAAGGGCUGUUCCCACCCUGUGUUACCAAUGCUAUUCUCCUUUCCCAAAGACAGCCUCUUUUGUAGCAUCCUAAGACAGACCUGAAGUCCAGAGGCUGCUCAAUUUCUUGGAUGAAACAAAUGAUAAGCCAGGAGCGGUGGCUCACGCCUGUAAUCCCAGCACUUUGGGAGGCCGAGGCGGGUGGAUCACGAGGUCGGGAGAUCGAGACCAUCCUGGCUAACACAGUGAAACACCGUCUCUACUAAAAAUAAAAAAAAAUAGCUGGGUGUGGUGGUGGGCGCCUGUAGUCCCAGCUACUCGGAAGGCUGAGGCAGGAGAAUGGCGUGAACCCAGGAGGCGGAGCUUGCAGUGAGCCGAGAUGGUGCCACUGCACUCCAGCCUGGGCAACAGAGCGAGAAUCUGUUUCAAAAAAAAAAAAAAAAAAAAAAGACAAAUGAUAAUAGGCAAGCCUUUGGAAGGACCUUUGUGUAGCCUUAAAUAAGAUAAACUUGGAAAGGUAAAGAACAGAAUACUAGUAGUUGGGGAGAUCAGGGUUCUAGUUCUAUUUCUUUCACACUUGAGCAUGUUGCUUUUUACCUUACUGAACCUCCAUUUCUCCCUUCUUUAAAAUGGUACUUGUCUCGGGCUUGUCUUUUUCUUACAGGGUUUAAUUCAGUGAGAGAAUGCAUAUGGGCAAGUAUCUUUUAAAUUGUAGAGCACUGUGCGCAUGGGGCUAGGAUUAUUGUUGUAUACAAGUGAGCCAGAGACCCUGGAAGAAUCUGGGUUGGAUAAUGGCAUUGCAGGAGAAAGGAACUAAAAUUUAUGAAACAUCUACUACAUGCCAGGUACCAAGCCAGGUGCUUUUCUGUUUGUAAAGGAUAAAAUGUCAGCCUUGCAACACUCCGGUGAGGUAGGCAUUAUUACUCCCAUUUUACCUGUAGGAAAACUGAGGCUUUAAGAGGUCUAGGGACUUGUAAUGUUCCAGAGACUACCUCUAGAGCCCAGGGUUUCUGUCAGGUAUUUGUGAAGAGAUCUUAAGAAUGUCCUAUGGUUUCUAUUGGGGUUUUCUAGCCCACUCCCUGCCUCACUCCAGCCUCUCUCCUCUGGUGGGGAUGAGACUGUCUCUUGUUGGCUUCAUGUCUCAGUCCUGAACUCUUUAUCCUCAGAUUUCCUUGGAGUGCACUGGGCACAAUUAGGUGCCCUUGUUUGGCCUUUAGCUGAUGGGGAGCCCUUUGGGUCAGCCACCUUUUGGCUGAUAGUAAGGAUGUCCUGCUACCCUGGGGUGCUGGUAAGGAGAGCCAGGGAUUUAUAGCUAGCCAGACAGACUUGGCUCUUGGUCAAGGUCAUGCAGCUAGAAAAUAGCAGUUGGUUCCUUUCUUUGAGACUCAGUUUCCUCAUUCAUAAAAUGGGUUUAAUAAUGCUUAACUUGCAUGUGUCUCUUGUCCAGUGUGCUGGUAAAUGUUUAACAAUCAACUCUUCGGCAAAUCCAUGAUUUUUACUGUUUGCCAAUUCCCAUGGUAUAAAUACUCCCACCAUGGCUGAUUUCAGGUUACCAAUAUGCAGUCCUUGAUGGAGGAGUUGGGAAGAGAUGUGCAUGAUCAGCUCUAGUGCAAGCUGGUUCUAGUGCACCAUUGCUAGUCACACCUAUUUUAGACUCCUACCCUCACCCUCCAACAUACUCACAUCUGUAUGCAAAUGCAGCAUCCUCUCAACCAUGCCUCUUCUUUUCCUCAAGUUCCAAGAGCAUCAAGGAAAGAGAGAGCUUCAUUUAAGGUCUGCUCCUUGCCUGAAAGUUCUUCCAGGAAAGAGUGAAUGUGGAGUGUUUAAGACGCAGAGAACUCAAGAGGGCUUUGAGUGGGGCCCUAAUUAUAGCAUUGUGAUCAUCAUGCUUUGGCUGCUGAAGUAUCUGAACUGUCUGUUUUCUCCCACUGUUUGAUUCUUAGCUAGAUGGGAGGAUGGUUGAAGAUCCUGGACAAUGGUCUGAGGGUCUGGUGCACUUAGCGUUCUGAUUGUAAUUUCAAAGUCUCCUCCUCUUCCUGCCUGCAGACCUUACUUUGCUGGGUGCUAACCUCAAGGUUCCUGUCAUGGGGAUCUCUGGGCCAGAAAGCAUUUUGGAUGACCAGAGAUCCCUGGUCCUGUUCUCUCAUUUCAACAGCAUCAAGGCCAUGUGUUGUUUCUUUGAACUUUUCAGAUGGAAAGAAUCACCUGAGGCAUUUGUUAAAAUGCUAAUUCCCCAGCGUCUUCUCUGGAGAGUCCAUUUCAGUAAGCUUGGGGUGGUGUCCAGAAGUCUGGACUUUUUGACCAGUGCCAAAUUCUUAUGAUCAGUGUGCGUGUGACCACCAUGGAUGCAGAGCUGGAGUUUGCCAUCCAGCCCAACACCACCGGGAAGCAGCUAUUUGACCAGGUGGUGAAAACUAUUGGCUUGAGGGAAGUUUGGUUCUUUGGUCUGCAGUACCAGGACACUAAAGGUUUCUCCACCUGGCUGAAACUCAAUAAGAAGGUGACUGCCCAGGAUGUGCGGAAGGAAAGCCCCCUGCUCUUUAAGUUCCGUGCCAAGUUCUACCCUGAGGAUGUGUCCGAGGAAUUGAUUCAGGACAUCACUCAGCGCCUGUUCUUUCUGCAAGUGAAAGAGGGCAUUCUCAAUGAUGAUAUUUACUGCCCGCCUGAGACCGCUGUGCUGCUGGCCUCGUAUGCUGUCCAGUCUAAGUAUGGCGACUUCAAUAAGGAAGUGCAUAAGUCUGGCUACCUGGCCGGAGACAAGUUGCUCCCGCAGAGAGUCCUGGAACAGCACAAACUCAACAAGGACCAGUGGGAGGAGCGGAUCCAGGUGUGGCAUGAGGAACACCGUGGCAUGCUCAGGGAGGAUGCUGUCCUGGAAUAUCUGAAGAUUGCUCAAGAUCUGGAGAUGUAUGGUGUGAACUACUUCAGCAUCAAGAACAAGAAAGGCUCAGAGCUGUGGCUGGGGGUGGAUGCCCUGGGUCUCAACAUCUAUGAGCAGAAUGACAGACUAACUCCCAAGAUAGGCUUCCCCUGGAGUGAAAUCAGGAACAUCUCUUUCAAUGAUAAGAAAUUUGUCAUCAAGCCCAUUGACAAAAAAGCCCCGGACUUCGUCUUCUAUGCUCCCCGGCUGCGGAUUAACAAGCGGAUCUUGGCCUUGUGCAUGGGGAACCAUGAACUAUACAUGCGCCGUCGCAAGCCUGAUACCAUUGAGGUGCAGCAGAUGAAGGCACAGGCCCGGGAGGAGAAGCACCAGAAGCAGAUGGAGCGUGCUAUGCUGGAAAAUGAGAAGAAGAAGCGUGAAAUGGCAGAGAAGGAGAAAGAGAAGAUUGAACGGGAGAAGGAGGAGCUGAUGGAGAGGCUGAAGCAGAUCGAGGAACAGACUAAGAAGGCUCAGCAAGAACUGGAAGAACAGACCCGUAGGGCUCUGGAACUUGAGCAGGAACGGAAGCGUGCCCAGAGCGAGGCUGAAAAGCUGGCCAAGGAGCGUCAAGAAGCUGAAGAGGCCAAGGAGGCCUUGCUGCAGGCCUCCCGGGACCAGAAAAAGACUCAGGAACAGCUGGCCUUGGAAAUGGCAGAGCUGACAGCUCGAAUCUCCCAGCUGGAGAUGGCCCGACAGAAGAAGGAGAGUGAGGCUGUGGAGUGGCAGCAGAAGGCCCAGAUGGUACAGGAAGACUUGGAGAAGACCCGUGCUGAGCUGAAGACUGCCAUGAGUACACCUCAUGUGGCAGAGCCUGCUGAGAAUGAGCAGGAUGAGCAGGAUGAGAAUGGGGCAGAGGCUAGUGCUGACCUACGGGCUGAUGCUAUGGCCAAGGACCGCAGUGAGGAGGAACGUACCACUGAGGCAGAGAAGAAUGAGCGUGUGCAGAAGCACCUGAAGGCCCUCACUUCGGAGCUGGCCAAUGCCAGAGAUGAGUCCAAGAAGACUGCCAAUGACAUGAUCCAUGCUGAGAACAUGCGACUGGGCCGAGACAAAUACAAGACCCUGCGCCAGAUCCGGCAGGGCAACACCAAGCAGCGCAUUGACGAAUUUGAGUCUAUGUAAUGGGCACCCAGCCUCUAGGGACCCCUCCUCCCUUUUUCCUUGUCCCCACACUCCUACACCUAACUCACCUAACUCAUACUGUGCUGGAGCCACUAACUAGAGCAGCCCUGGAGUCAUGCCAAGCAUUUAAUGUAGCCAUGGGACCAAACCUAGCCCCUUAGCCCCCACCCACUUCCCUGGGCAAAUGAAUGGCUCACUAUGGUGCCAAUGGAACCUCCUUUCUCUUCUCUGUUCCAUUGAAUCUGUAUGGCUAGAAUAUCCUACUUCUCCAGCCUAGAGGUACUUUCCACUUGAUUUUGCAAAUGCCCUUACACUUACUGUUGUCCUAUGGGAGUCAAGUGUGGAGUAGGUUGGAAGCUAGCUCCCCUCCUCUCCCCUACCACUGUCUUCUUCAGGGUCCUGAGAUUUACACGGUUGGAGUGUUAUGCGGUCUAGGGAAUGAGACAGGACCUAGGAUAUCUUCUCCAGGAUGUCAACUGACCUAAAAUUUGCCCUCCCAUCCCGUUUAGAGUUAUUUAGGCUUUGUAACGAUUGGGGGAUAAAAAGAUGUUCAGUCAUUUUUGUUUCUACCUCCCAGAUCGGAUCUGUUGCAAACUCAGCCUCAAUAAGCCUUGUCGUUGACUUUAGGGACUCAAUUUCUCCCCAGGGUGGAUGGGGGAAAUGGUGCCUUCAAGACCUUCACCAAACAUACUAGAAGGGCAUUGGCCAUUCUAUUGUGGCAAGGCUGAGUAGAAGAUCCUACCCCAAUUCCUUGUAGGAGUAUAGGCCGGUCUAAAGUGAGCUCUAUGGGCAGAUCUACCCCUUACUUAUUAUUCCAGAUCUGCAGUCACUUCGUGGGAUCUGCCCCUCCCUGCUUCAAUACCCAAAUCCUCUCCAGCUAUAACAGUAGGGAUGAGUACCCAAAAGCUCAGCCAGCCCCAUCAGGACUCUUGUGAAAAGAGAGGAUAUGUUCACACCUAGCGUCAGUAUUUUCCCUGCUAGGGGUUUUAGGUCUCUUCCCCUCUCAGAGCUACUUGGGCCAUAGCUCCUGCUCCACAGCCAUCCCAGCCUUGGCAUCUAGAGCUUGAUGCCAGUAGGCUCAACUAGGGAGUGAGUGCAAAAAGCUGAGUAUGGUGAGAGAAGCCUGUGCCCUGAUCCAAGUUUACUCAACCCUCUCAGGUGACCAAAAUCCCCUUCUCAUCACUCCCCUCCAAAGAGGUGACUGGGCCCUGCCUCUGUUUGACAAACCUCUAACCCAGGUCUUGACACCAGCUGUUCUGUCCCUUGGAGCUGUAAACCAGAGAGCUGCUGGGGAUUCUGGCCUAGUCCCUUCCACACCCCCACCCCUUGCUCUCAACCCAGGAGCAUCCACCUCCUUCUCUGUCUCAUGUGUGCUCUUCUUCUUUCUACAGUAUUAUGUACUCUACUGAUAUCUAAAUAUUGAUUUCUGCCUUCCUUGCUAAUGCACCAUUAGAAGAUAUUAGUCUUGGGGCAGGAUGAUUUUGGCCUCAUUACUUUACCACCCCCACACCUGGAAAGCAUAUACUAUAUUACAAAAUGACAUUUUGCCAAAAUUAUUAAUAUAAGAAGCUUUCAGUAUUAGUGAUGUCAUCUGUCACUAUAGGUCAUACAAUCCAUUCUUAAAGUACUUGUUAUUUGUUUUUAUUAUUACUGUUUGUCUUCUCCCCAGGGUUCAGUCCUCAAGGGGCCAUCCUGUCCCACCAUGCAGUGCCCCUAGCUUAGAGCCUCCCUCAAUUCCCCCUGGCCACCACCCCCCACUCUGUGCCUGACCUUGAGGAGUCUUGUGUGCAUUGCUGUGAAUUAGCUCACUUGGUGAUAUGUCCUAUAUUGGCUAAAUUGAAACCUGGAAUUGUGGGGCAAUCUAUUAAUAGCUGCCUUAAAGUCAGUAACUUACCCUUAGGGAGGCUGGGGGAAAAGGUUAGAUUUUGUAUUCAGGGGUUUUUUGUGUACUUUUUGGGUUUUUUAAAAAUUGUUUUUGGAGGGGUUUAUGCUCAAUCCAUGUUCUAUUUCAGUGCCAAUAAAAUUUAGGAAGACUUCA